AUUCGUGGCCGUCUGGGGCCAGAGCUGUGGACCGCGGCAUGGCCGAGCCGGGGCCGGAGCCCGGGCGUGCCUGGCGGGUGCUCGCCCUGUGCGGGGUGGCCGUGUUCCUGGCUGCGGCAGCAGCCGGCGGGGCCCUGGUAGCCUGGAAUCUGGCCGCCUCGGCUGCUCGGGGACCUCGCUGCCCGGAGCCAGGGGCCAAUGCCACGGCGCCGCCCGGGGACCCGCCGCCUGGGGUCGACGACCUGCGGCGCCGGCUGGCAGAGGCUGCCGAGCGGGAGGAGGCCCUAGCCAGGCAGCUGGACCAGGCGGAAAGUAUCCGGCACGAGUUGGAGAAGGCAUUAAAGGCCUGUGAAGGCCGCCAGAGCCGGCUUCAGACCCAACUAACGACACUGAAGAUUGAGAUGGACGAAGCCAAGGCACAGGGGACCCAGAUGGGGGCCGAGAACGGGGCGCUGACAGAGGCCCUGGCGCGCUGGGAGGCGGCGGCCACGGAGUCUACGCGGCGGCUGGACGAGGCUCUGCGGCGCGCAGGCGUGGCGGAGGCCGAGGGCGAAGCCUGUGCGGCCCGGGAGGCGGCGCUGCGCGAACGCCUUAACGUCCUGGAAGCCGAGAUGAGCCCACAGCGCAGAGUGCCCCGGCCGCGUCCCCGCUCGGGGUCCCGACCCCGGCCCAGCCCUCGCUCGCGCUCUCGCUCCGGACCCUCCGGGGGCUGCCGGCGGCCGGCGCGGCGCGCACGAGGGUGAGUCGGCCCCCUGCCGGAAGGGGGCGUCGGCCUGGAGGACACAUAUGGGGGGGGGGUCUGCGGGGACGUGUAUAGAGGCACCCCCACGCUGGAUGCGACACUCAGCUUUAGACCCUGGAGACGUCCUGAACGGAAACUGCACAGAAAGGUGCCUCAGCCCUCUCUCCCCCACCAUGUAAAGUGCUUAUUCUACAGACAGGGAAACUGAGGCCCAAGUGAUCAUGCAGUGAGCUAGUGCUUAGCUGGGAUUUGAAGUCCCCUCUAACAACAAUGUUGCCGUCAUCCCACAGAUAUGAGGACUGGAGGUCUAGCCCUGGCUCAGGAAAAACCGGAAAGGGUCACUUUCCCUCUUUGGGUUUCAGUUUACCCUAUCUGUAAAAUGGGUGAUUGGACUCAUGAUAGGGAGCUGAUUUGACAACAAAAGCUGACAAAGGUGGCACAAUAGGAAAACCGCAAAUCCCUAACCCUGUGAGAAGGGUACAAAACUCCCAGAUGGAAUUUAAACAAAAAGAACCAAGUAACAUGUUUGUUUUGGUUUGGUUUUGAGAUGGAGUUUUGCUGUUGUCGCCCAGGCUGGAGUGCAGUGGCACAAUUUGGGCUCACUGCAACCUUCACCUCCCAGGUUCAAGCAAUUCUCCUGCCUCAGCCUCCCAGGUAGCUGGGAUUACAGGCCCCCACCACUACGCCCAGCUGAUUUUUGUAUUUUUAGUAGAGACGGGGUUACACCAUGUUGGCCAGGCUGGUCUCGAACUCCUGAGCUUAGGUGAUCCGCCCACCCGGCCUCCCAAAGUGCUGGGAUUACAGGUGUGAGCCACCGCUCCCAGCCCAUGUUUUUAACCUACACUGCAACAAAGGUGACUUAUGCCUGAGACAGAGCAAUGGUUCAAUAUUGCCAAGUCUGUUAAUUGCUAUACUAAUAGAUCAAAUGAGGAAAUGUAUAAAUUGUGGGGGAAAAAACACAUCAAAAUCAGUGCCAAGGUGAGGACGUCCACUGUCAAGUAGUUUUUUUUCUGGGAGUACAAGCCAAUGCAAUUACACAAGAAAAAUAAAAGCUACAACUAAAAGGAAGAGAAUCUGUAGGUUGAAUCACAAGAAAGAGCUGUUUAUAUGGGUCAAAAAUCAUUGAAAUAUGGACAAUUUUAUAUUGCUCAAUUUCACAUGAAUGUAUUAGUGGGUUUUCUUGUUUUUCUAACCUUUAAACAUUUUUAGCUUGUUAUCUAAAUUUAACCUUUAUAUUUGGCAUAACUUCAGACUUACAGAAAAUUUGGUGGAUUAAUCUCCAACUCCUUAACAACACAAAGGUUAUGGGCACCAGUUCUCCAUGCAGUUGAAAAUUCACACAUAACUUUGACUCCUCCAAACUCAAAGCUGGCCAGGUGUGGUGGCUCACGCCUGUAAUCCCAACAUUUUGGGAGGCCACAGCAAGAAGAUCACUUGAGCCCAGGAGUUCAAGACCAGCCUGGGCACCAUAGCAAGAACCUGUCUCUACAAAUAAUAUCAAUAAUUAGCUGAGCAUGGUGACAUGCAUCUGUAGCCCCAGCUACUUGGGAGGCUGAGGCGGGAGGAUCACUUGAGCCCAGGACGUCAAGUUUGCAGUGAGCCAUGAUCACACCACUGCACUUCAGUCCUCUGAGUGACAGAGCAAGACCCGGUCUCAAAAAUUAAACAUGAAAAAUUAAAGCUAUAAAAAAAUUAUUAAGAAAAUCAUGCUGGGCACAGUGGUUCAUGCCUGUAAGCCCAAUACUUUGGGAGGCUAAGGCGGGAGGAUCUCUUGAGCCCUGAAGUUCAAGACCAGUCUGGGCAACAUAGGGAGACCCUGUCUCUACAAAUAAUUGUUUCAAAAUUCUUUGGGAGGCUGAGGCGGGUGGAUCACUUGAGCUCAGGUGUUUGAGACCAGCCUGGGCAACAUGGUGAAACCCAUUCUCUACCAAAAAUACAAAAUAUUAGCUGGGCAUGGUGGCAUGCACCUGUGGUCCCAUCUACUUCGGAGACUGAGGUGGGAGGAUCACUUGAGCCUGGGAGGCAGAGGCUGCAGUGAGCCAAGAUCGUGCUAGGGUGACUGGAGCAAAACCCCUUCAAGAAAAGAAAGAAGAGAAAGAAAGAAAAAAGAAAGACAAAAAAGAAAAGAAAGAAAGAGAAGAAAGUAGCCAGGCUUGGUGGCAUGCACCUGUGGUCCCAGCUACUUGGGAGGCUGAAGCAGGAAGAUCACUUAAGCCCAGGAGGUGGAAGCUGCAGUGAGCCAUGAUCAUGCCACUGCACUCCAGCCUAGGUGACUGAGUGAGAUCCUGUCUCAAAAAAAAAAAAAAAAAAAAAAAAGGAAAAAAAGAGCCCGGGGGUGGCUCACGCCUGUAAUCCCAGCACUUUGGGAGGCCGAGGCGGGCGGAUCACGAGGUCAGGAGAUCGAGACCAUCCUGGCUAACACGGUGAAACCCUUUCUCUAUUAAAAAUACAAAAAAUUAGCCGGGCAUGGUGGUGGGCAUCUGUAGUCCCAGCUACUUGGGAGGCUGAGGCGGGAGAAUGGCAUGAACCUGGGAGGCGGAGCUUGCAGUGAUCUGAGAUCGCACCACUGCACUCCAGCCUGGGUGACAGAGUGAGACUCUGUCUCAAAAAAAAUAAAAAUAAAUAGAAAAGAAAGACAGAAAAAGAAAAAGUGUCUGUCCAUCCACAGUGGAACGCUAUGCAACCACCAUUUAAACAGCCAAAGCAGAUCUUCUCUAAGAUAUGUUAAUGUGAAAAGCAGGAGAUUGAUAAGUUGUGUACUUUCUUUCUUUCUUUCUUUUUUUUUCUUUUUGAGAUAGAGUCUUGCUUUUGUUGCCCAGGCUGGAGUGCAAUGGCGCAGUCUCAGCUCACUGCAACCUCCGCCUCUCGGGUUCAAACGAUUCUCUUGCCUCAGCCUCGAGUAACUGGAAUUACAGGCGCCCAUCACCAGACUCAGCUAGUUUUUUGUGUUUUUUAGUAAAGACGGGGUUUCACCAUGUUGGCCAGGCUGGUCUCGAAUUGCUAACCUCGGGUGAUCCACCCUCCUUGGCCUCCCAAAGUGCUGGGAUUACAGGCCUGAGCCGCUGUGCCCGGCCCCCGUUUUUGUGUGUGUGUGUGUGUGUAGGGCUUGGGGAGGGGACUUUUAUCCAAAUAUCUCUGAAGGAGAUGCUGGUCACAGCCUCCACCUCUGGGGAGCGAACCAGGGGUCUGGGAAUCGGUGGGGGACAUACUUGCACAUUUCUCUAUGUACCUUUUGUAAAAAUUGCAUUUUUAAAAACCAUGCACAUGUGUCACUUAUUACAAAUUAAAAAUUAAAAAUUGUUUUUAAAAAUGUC